AGCCCAGCCAGGCUGCCCUUCUUCCCUGCGGAGGGAGGGCCUGGGCGGUCGCGUUGGCGGGAGGGAGGUUACCUUUCCCAGUCUCGCUCUGGCCGCCUGAGCCAGGAGGAAGCAGCGGCGAGGUCUGCGGGAGGCAUGGCGGGAGCUCCGGACGAGCGCCGGCGGGGCCCCGCGGCAGGGGAGCAGCUGCAGCAGCAACACGUCUCUUGCCAGGUCUUCCCCGAGCGUCUGGCCCAGGGGAAUCCCCAGCAAGGGUUCUUCUCCAGCUUCUUCACCAGCAACCAGAAGUGCCAGCUUAGGCUCCUGAAGACGCUGGAGACAAAUCCAUAUGUCAAACUUCUGCUUGAUGCUAUGAAACACUCAGGUUGUGCUGUUAACAAAGAUAGACACUUUUCUUGCGAAGACUGUAAUGGAAAUGUCAGUGGAGGUUUUGAUGCUUCAACAUCUCAGAGAUGGGGUUUUGCUCUGUUGCCCAGGCUGGUCCCGAACUCCUGGGCUCAAGGAAUCUGCCUGCCUCAGCCUCUCAAAGUACUGGGAUUAUAGGCAUGAGCCACUGCACCCAACCUCAUUGUAUAUGCUCAUGACAACCUGGGUUUUUCUUCAUGACAACUGUCAUUGCAUAUAGUUUUGUGCCAGAAUAAUAUCCAUAAUCAGGCCCAUAUGAACAGAGUGGUCACACACGAGCUUAUUCAUGCAUUUGAUCAUUGUCGUGCCCAUGUCGACUGGUUCACCAACAUCAGACAUUUGGCGUGCUCAGAGGUUCGAGCUGCUAACCUUAGUGGAGACUGCUCACUUGUCAAUGAAAUAUUCAGGUUACAUUUUGGAUUAAAACAACACCACCAGACUUGUGUGCGAGACAGAGCCACUCUUUCUAUCCUGGCUGUUAGGAAUAUCAGCAAAGAAGUAGCUAAAAAGGCUGUUGAUGAAGUUUUUGAAUCUUGUUUCAAUGACCAUGAACCUUUUGGAAGGAUCCCACAUAACAAGACUUAUGCAAGAUAUGCUCACAGAGACUUUGAAAACCGUGAUCGGUAUUAUUCAAAUAUAUGAGCACAAUGACAUUUUUAUAUUACAGAGCUUCCAUCAUCAUGAAGAAAAAAAAAUUUGGUUCUCAAGUGAACAAACAUAUAAAAUGUAAACAAUCCCUACAAUCCAGAUAAAACAGAGAAGACUGUGAUUCUAGCAUAUUAUCAGAAAAAGUAACUAUGGCAAAAAAUGAAACUGCUUUAAACUCCAAGGCAGAAAUUGUAUCUUUAUAGCUAACCAUUUAGUAAAUAAAUACAUUACAUUUUUGUAUUUUAGUCAUUUGUUUUUAUUACAUGUGAUUAUUUUAAAAUUUGAUUAUGAAACCUGUGAAGUGUGCUCUUCCAUGAUGUUGAUAGGUGACCACUGUUGGUAUUUACAUUAAAUGUAAAGAAAUGUGUACUGAUCUCAUUGUAGGAUACUUAUUGAGCUGUUGUUAUGAUGAAAAUUGGAAAUAAUUCAUUCAGUGGUCAAUGCUAUCCUCUCCCUAUUCUUCUUUUAUCAUAUAUGUGGGACCCAUAUGGCCUAAUUUUCUGGGGACAGUCCUGGUUAGAUCUUUUUCUUUUUAAUAAAGGCAGUGCUCGAAUUUUAGCUCCAGAUCGACUGCAAGAACAAACCAGCAAUACUGAGAGGACCCACAGACCCUCUGAAGGAAGCGACUGCUCCUACAGUGCCCAGGAGACACCCCAAAUACUGUGAGUGCCCAACUGCAGAAGUGGGAAAGGGAGACCCUCCUCUCCCACACACACCCCCCCACUGGAGAAACUGAAGGUCUGUUUGUGGGAGAAGUUUCCGACCUUACCUGGAGCUGAGUUAAUUUAGAGAGCCGAGCGAAAUACAGGGGUAGAGCAAGCAGCAGGAAGGCCCAGGGAGCUCGCUGGGUCCCCAAGCAGCCCAUUCCUGCCUGUCACCACAGAGAUCCAUUGCAAGGGCAGCCAGAAGAGCAGCGGGUAAAACUCCACAGGGAGAAGGACAUCUCUAGCUGAACUUUGUAACUAUUUCAAUGGGGCAAGAAGCCUCCCGGCCAGAACUUGGGAGAGGGCACAAAUCCCAUGUGCAGAAUCCACAGAGGGGAAGAACCAAGCUCUUUUCUUUCACAGCUGGGAGGUGGGUAGCCUGGGGCAAGUUUUCAAGCCUGUCUCACCCACCACCUGGAAGCAGACUUGGGGCUGUGGUGGGGGGCAUGGUGGGAGUGAGACUGGCCCUUCGGCUUGUGUGGGAGCUGGGUGAGGCCUGUGACUGCCGGCUUUCCCCUACUUCCCUGACAACCUGCAUGACUCCCCAGAGGCAGUCAUAAUCCUCCUAGGGACACAACUCCAGUGACCUGGGAAUCUCACCCUCAUCUCCCACAACAGUCACAGCAAGACCUGCCCAAGGAGAGUCUGAGCUCAGACAUGUCUAUCCCUGCCCCGACCUGAUGUUCCUUCCCUACCCACCCUGGUAUCUGAACAAAAAGGGCAUACAAUCUUGGGAGUUCUAGGGCCCCACUCACCACAAGUUCUUCUCCAUACUACCACAACUGAUGCUCUCUGGAAAGCGCUACCUCCUGGCAGGAGGCCAGCCAGCACAAAAAUAGAGCCUUCAACCACCAAAGCUAAGAACCCUCAUGGAGUCCAUUGCACCCCCCCUGCCACCUCCACUGGAACAGGUGCUGGUAUCCACAGCCGAGAGACCCAUAGACGGUUCACAUCACAGGAUUCUGUGCAGGCAACCCCCAGUACCAGCAUGGAGCUGGGUAGACUCACUGGGUGGCUAGACCCAGAAGAGAGACAACAAUCACAGCAGUUUGGCUUACAGGAAGCCACAUCCAUCGGAAAAGGGGGAGGGUAUACAUCAAGGGAACACCCUGUGGGACAAAGGAACCUGAACAAUGGCCUUCAGCCCUAGACCUUCCCUUUGACAGAGACUACCCAAAUGAGAAGGAACCAGAAAACUAACCCUGGUAAUAUGACAAAACAAAAGCUCUUUAACACCCACAAAAAAAUCACACUAGUUCACCAGCAAUGGAUUCAAACCAAGAAGAAAUCCCUGAUUUACCUGAAAAAGAAUUCAGGAGGUUAGUUAUUAAGCUAAUCAGGGAGGCACCAGAGAAAGGCAAAGCCCAGUGCAAGGAAAUCCAAAAAAUGAUAUAAGAAGUGAAGGGAGAAAUAUUCAAGGAAAUGGAGAGCUUAAAGAAAAAAGAAUAAAAAAUUCAGGAAACUUUGGACACACUUUUAGAAAUGCAAAAUGCUCUGGAAAAUCUCAGCAAUAGAAUUGAACAAGUAGAAGAAAGAAAUUCAGAGCUU